GGUACACCUGUCGGCCCUUGCGAAGACCGGAGAGUAGGACGGGGCCGCCGUCCUUGAGGGAGUCCAGGGCCAGCUGAUCGAAAGUCAGGAUCUUGGCCCCCACCCUGAGGAUGCCGCUGUGGGCCGGCUGGUCACGGGCAGCGCACACACCUUAAGUUUGGGCACCUCCUGAACCCUCGCGUCAUCCGUUAAGCGUCCCCACAACCACGGCCGUUUUGUUUUCCCAGCCAGGAAGCUUCAUCUUCCGGAUCAUCCGGGAAACGGACAGAGGUGGCCGGUUGGUGCGACUCAUAAACAACCUCUUCAGCACAACCUGGUUGAAUGUGGAGUUAGUUCGUCUGGACGGUAACCUGUACAGCUUGACCAACAAACAGCCUCAGUUAGAUAUCCUGGCUCUUGGGCUCUUUGCGCCGAACCUUUAGGUCCUUCUUGUGGCGGACGUCAGCUCCCAUGAUGGCGCUUCCUGCUUGGCCAGAUGCAGUGAGCCAGGCCCAAGGACGCCCCGGCCACCCUGACGCACCCCCCAACAUCUACGAGGGGGGCCUGGGGUCCCCGCAGCCGCAGUGCCCCAGUGCCCAGGGAAGCAAGCCCAAGAACUUCCGGCUGCGCCACCUCCGGGGCCUGGGCCUCUACCUGGAGAGCCACCCGCCACCCACUGGCCAGUGUGAGAGCCACUGGCUGGGCCGGCUUAUGGCUGGGGGCUGCCUGCCACAGCCUGAGGGCACAGCCUGGGCCCUGGACCUGCCACAGGGGACUCUGGGCCCACGUAACAGCCUCUGUUCAGCCCUUCUGGAAGCCCGAUUGCCCAGGGACAGCCUGGGAAGCAGUGCUUCCAGUUCCAGCAUGGACCCAGACAAGGGUGCCCUCCCCCAGCCUAGUCCUUCUAGGCUCAGGCCCAAGAGGUCCUGGGGGACCUGGGAAGAGGCCAUGUGUCCCUUGUGCAAGAGAACCCGCUCUGGGGCCCUGGAGAGGCCAUAGGGAUCCCGAGUGCCAGGACUGGGUACAGGAGGGGCAGGAUGGCCGAGGAGGCAGCCUGAGCAGGAGGGGCUCGGCCCCCGGCAGUGGCCCUGCCACAUGGGGUGGCCCAGGCAGCGGCCCAGCGCCCAGGCCUGGGCCUCGGGAGAAUGUGAUGGGGAGAGGGAGGAGGAGGAGGUUCCGAGGGAGGGGCAGAAGCAAUAGAAGCAUGGCCGUGCCCUUGCAGCCUGCUUAGACUCCAGUCAGCCACUUGUACCUGGGAGGCCGGGCUGAGUGCAGAAUCAGGCCCCCCCGCCACCGCCUCCCUGAGAGGCCGGGGAGCCCACAGCUCUGAUCUCAAUAAAAGCCAAGGCCUGCA